CUGGUUUGGGGGCAAGGUCUCAUGGGAAAGGUCAUGUCUCUCGAAGAAAGGUUAUAAACCCUGAGAUAUGAGGGUUGGGCGAGACAUCCGAGCCUGUUUCGUUCCGUGUUGGGACCAGGAAUAACCCUGACUUCUGAGCUUUCAUAACCCCAGGAUCCUCCAGAAAAUUUGCGGCGCGCUGAGGGAAAACCUUGCUGGCAAGUCGGGACUGUGUGGCAGCGGCUAUUUUUCUUUUCCCACCCAGCACGUUUUCGGGCUGGGGACAUAGGGUUCAGUUGAGAUACGGAGGCUUCCUUCGGGAUAUUGGGUUCUCUGAAGUGCGGAUGGACUAGGGCAGGGCUGAGACCCCAUUCAUUCACUCAUUUGUUUAGCUCUCCUUUAUGCCCGGCGCAGAAGAUACCCCUUAGGGUCCCAAGGCCCUUCCUGUAGUUAAGUUCCUUCCUUAAGGUCAUUCAGCUGGGGCAAAGCUGGGGACUCGACACCUUUCUAUGCUAACCAUUGAGCUGCCUCCACUUUGAGCAGCUCAGUGGAUGAAUAUAGUAUCUUGAGGAUACCUUUGAUUUGUGCAGGGUUUUCUUGUGCAGGUUUGUGACCCAGGUCAGCUUAGGUCAGGAUGCUGUACUGCUUGCCACAAAAUAGCCUGUACUGUCGCGUCGUUUUUUCUUGUGAACAGACUGUUUGGCAUAGCCGUAGAGAGGGGUCUGAGACAUGAAUUUAGUGAUACAGCGUUGAUUUGUUUGUGUAAUGAAGCUGUUCAAGUGGAAAGAACUGAGUUGUAGUCCCUGCUUCACUAGUACUAGAAGGAUUUUUUAAACCUUUUUGAACCUAUUUUGCCUUAUCUGUAAAAUGGAAAUAAUAUCAACCUGGAAGAAGCUGUACAUUGGAAUGCGUUUACAGUCAUUGUAAUGGAAGCAAAAUACAUGAAGGAAAAACUGUUAUUUGUAUCCCUGCUUAUUGCACCUGACGACUAGUUGCAGAUGGUUUUGUUUACCUAAGAAAACUUGUGAUAUAAAUGAAAAAAACACCUGUUUUCCUAGAGUCAUUGGUUACAAAUAUGCUUCGUCUAAGAGCUAUUUGUCCAUUCUCCUGGAGAGUGUUUCAAUUUCGACCCAUCAGUUGUGAACCACUAAUUAUUCAGAUGAAUAAGUGUACAGAUGAGGAGCAAAUGUUUGGUUUUAUUGAAAGAAACAAAGCCAUACUUUCAGAAAAGCAAGUGGGAUGUGCAUUUGAUAUGCUUUGGAAGCUUCAAAAGCAGAAGACCAGCCUGUUAAAAAAUGCUGAGUAUGUCAGAGACCAUCCUCAAUUUCUUACUCUUCAUAAUUUAGCUACAAAUAAAUUCAAAUUAAUGAAUGACGAUACCCUGGUGAAUGUGUUAUACGUCACACAACAGUUUGCUGGUGAGGCCCAUGACCCGCUAGUUGAAGCACUAGUUACAGAAGCAUGGAGAAGGCUAGAAAGGUUUGAUAUUAAACUGCUCUCAGAAUUUUCCUCUUGCCUAGCAGAUCAGCAUUUGUAUUUUAGUCCAUUAAUGGGAAAAAUAGCUGAUAUUGUUCAUAGGAACUUGGAAACCACACAGGACUUAAGUUCCUUGUCUGUCUUGAUGGUCAACAUAUCUUCUUUAAUAUCACGACAUUUUCAACAACAACUGGUGAACAAAACAGAACUUCUUUUUGACACCAUAGAUUCUUCUGAGGUCAACGUUGCAAAAAGCAUAGCAAAGUUUCUUCGAAAUGUUAGAUAUCGUUAUCAACCACUAUUAGAAAGAUGUAAUAACGUAUUUUUAAGUAAUGUGGACCACCUUGAUUUGGAUUCCAUCAGUAAAAUACUUAGUGUAUACAAAUUUCUACAAUUUAAUAGUUUUGAAUUUAUUAUAAUGGCUAAAAAGAAGCUAACUGAAAUGAUUCCUCUGUGUAAUCAUCCUGCUAGCUUUGUAAAAUUGUUUGUAGCAUUGGGACCCAUUGCAGGACCUGAAGAAAAGAAACAACUUAAAUCAACUAUGUUAUUGAUGUCAGAGGACCUAACUGGCGAGCAAGCCCUGGCAGUGUUGGGAGCAAUGGGAGAUAUGGAAAGCAGAAACUCAUGUCUGAUUAAAAGAGUUACUUCAGUUCUGCAUAAACAUUUGGAUGGCUAUAAACCAUUAGAGUUGUUGAAGAUAACUCAAGAAUUAACUUUUCUGCAUUUCCAAAGGAAGGAGUUUUUUGCGAAACUUAGAGAAUUACUGCUUAGUUAUUUGAAAAAUAGUUUCAUACCAACUGAGGUGUCUGUUCUGGUCCGUGCUAUUUCCCUGCUCCCUUCUCCUCACUUGGACGAAGUGGGGAUAUCCCGAAUUGAAGCCGUUUUACCACAGUGUGACCUAAAUAACCUGAGUAGUUUUGCCACAUCUGUUUUAAGAUGGAUUCAGCAUGAUCACAUGUAUUUGGAUAAUAUGACUGCGAAACAACUGAAACUACUUCAAAAAUUAGAUCACUAUGGUCGUCAGAGACUACAACACAGCAACAGUUUGGAUCUGUUACGGAAGGAACUUAAAUCUCUCAAAGGAAACACGUUUCCUGAGUCACUUCUUGAAGAAAUGAUUGCUACUUUACAGCAUUUCAUGGAUGAUAUUAAUUACAUAAAUGUUGGGGAGAUUGCAUCUUUUAUUUCUAGUACUGAUUACCUCAGUACUUUGCUACUAGAUAGGAUAGCCUCAGUGGCUGUUCAGCAGAUUGAAAAGAUCCAUCCUUUUACAAUCCCUGCUAUUAUUCGUCCAUUCAGCGUAUUGAACUAUGAUCCACCUCAAAGGGAUGAAUUUUUGGGAACUUGCGUGCAACAUCUUAAUUCUUACUUAGGUAUAUUGGAUCCUUUUAUAUUAGUGUUUCUUGGUUUCUCUUUGGCCACACUUGAAUAUUUUCCAGAAGAUCUGCUAAAGGCAAUUUUUAACAUCAAAUUCUUAGCUAGAUUGGAUUCUCAACUUGAAAUUUUAUCUCCAUCUCGAAGUGCAAGAGUCCAGUUUCAUCUUAUGGAGUUAAAUAGAUCAGUCUGCUUGGAAUGCCCUGAGUUUCAGAUUCCAUGGUUUCAUGACCGCUUCUGUCAACAAUAUAAUAAAGGUAUUGGUGGCAUGGAUGGAACACAACAGCAGAUUUUUAAAAUGUUAGCAGAGGUACUAGGAGGAAUCAAUUGUGUAAAAGCCUCGGUUCUUACGCCUUAUUACCACAAAGUAGAUUUUGAGUGUAUCUUGGAUAAAAGAAAAAAACCUCUUCCGUAUGGAAGCCAUAAUAUAGCAUUGGGACAACUACCAGAAAUGCCCUGGGAAUCAAAUAUCGAAAUAGUUGGAUCAAGGCUGCCACCAGGGGCUGAAAGGAUUGCUUUGGAAUUUUUGGAUUCAAAAGCACUUUGUAGAAAUAUCCCUCACAUGAAAGGAAAAUCUGCUAUGAAAAAACGACAUUUGGAAAUUCUGGGGUAUCGUGUAAUUCAGAUUUCCCAGUUUGAAUGGAACUCUAUGGCACUGUCAACAAAGGAUGCUCGGAUGGACUACCUGAGAGAAUGUAUAUUUGGAGAAGUCAAGUCAUGUUUGUAGUUUUUAUUUAAAAUGAAUGUUAUCGUGUGUUACAUUUGGACCUAUUUUAAUAAAGUGGCCUGUCUCAAUUAAAAAAUAGGUACAAAUGUCCUAAGGUGGGAACAUGCCUGGCAUGUUUGAGAAUAACAAAGGAUCCAGUGUGGCUGGAGCAGAACAAGUGGGGAGUGGGGUGGGAGUGUAUAAGAGAAAAGAUAAGAGAUAACAGAGUCAAAUACAACCUCUUGGCUACUCUGAGCGAGAUGAGAAGCCAUUGGGGGCUUUUCAAGUAAGGAAUGAUAUGAAUUCACAUUUUAACUGCGUUACUUUGGCUACCUUGUUGAGAUAAGAAAAGACUACGAUGAGGCAAAUGUGUAAGAAAGAAAACUCUUUACGAGGUCAUUGCAAUAAUCCAGACAACAAUGGAUGGUGGCUUGGAGAGAGUGGUAGCAGUGGAGGUAAUAAGAAGUAGUCAGAUUUUUUGGAUGUAUGUUGAAGAUAAAGGCAACAGAAUUUGCUCACUGAUUGGAUAUGAGGUAUGAGACAAAUAGGAGUCAAGGAUAAUUCUAAGUUUUUGUCCUAAGCAACUAAGAGGAUGUCAUUAGCAUUAACUAAGAUGGGGAUAGUCUAUAGGAAGAGCAAGAUGGGGGGCAGGUGGUGGGGGUUGAUCACAAGUUUGUUUUAGAUAUGUUGAGUUUGUGAUGUCUUUUAAACAUCUAAGUGGAUAUAUCAAAUAGAGAAUUCAGUAAAUGAGCUUGGAGGUCAGGGAAGAGGUCCAGGCCCCAGAUAUAAAUGUAUAAAUGUCAGCAGUAUUCAAUGCCAUGAGAGUAGAUGAAAUCGCUUAAAAUGAGAUUAGAGAAGAGUGUGAAUGGAGGAGAGGUCUGAGGACUGAGUUUUCAAGUGCCCCAACAUUAAAAGAUUAAGAGGAAGAGGAGGAAUCAGGAAAGGAGACUGAGCAGGGAUGGCCAAUGAGGUAGGAGGAAGGAAGGUAAGUAAUACUUCCUAGAAGCCAAGUGGAUAAAGCAUUUCAAGGGGGAGGUGAGUAGUUGUAUCAGAUGCUGCUGAUAGGUCAGGAAAGAUGACAAAUGGGAAAUGGCUAUUAAAUUUAGCAACAUGAAAAUCAUUAGUACUUUGAAAAUAGUCGUUUUGAAGUGGUGCAUGUGAAAGCCUGACUGGUUCAAGAGAAAAUGGGAGGAGAUACAUUUUCUCCUAAAUGGAAGCAAAGAAAUGGGGUAGUAGCUGAGUGGACCAUCUUGACCUGGUGUAAUCCUACACAUUGAGGGAAUAAUGGCUUCUCCCUGUCUUACAACACAUUUAUUCAAUAAAAUGGUUACUAAGGGC